AGACUGCCAUAAGAUGGCGUCCGUGGCGGCUGCACGAGCAGUUCCCGUGGGCAGUGGGCUCAGGGGCCUGCAACGGACCCUACCUCUUGUAGUGAUUCUCGGGGCCACGGGCACCGGCAAAUCCACGCUGGCGUUGCAGCUAGGCCAGCGGCUCGGCGGUGAGAUCGUCAGCGCUGACUCCAUGCAGGUCUAUGAAGGCCUAGACAUCAUCACCAACAAGGUUUCUGCCCAAGAGCAGAGAAUCUGCCGGCACCACAUGAUCAGCUUUGUGGAUCCUCUUGUGACCAAUUACACAGUGGUGGACUUCAGAAAUAGAGCAACUGCUCUGAUUGAAGAUAUAUUUGCCCGAGACAAAAUUCCUAUUGUUGUGGGAGGAACCAAUUAUUACAUUGAAUCUCUGCUCUGGAAAGUUCUUGUCAAUACCAAGCCCCAGGAGAUGGGCACUGAGAAAGUGAUUGACCGAAAAGUGGAGCUUGAAAAGGAGGAUGGUCUUGUACUUCACAAACGCCUAAGCCAGGUGGACCCAGAAAUGGCUGCCAAGCUGCAUCCACAUGACAAACGCAAAGUGGCCAGGAGCUUGCAAGUUUUUGAAGAAACAGGAAUCUCUCAUAGUGAAUUUCUCCAUCGUCAACAUACGGAAGAAGGUGGUGGUCCCCUUGGAGGUCCUCUGAAGUUCUCUAACCCUUGCAUCCUUUGGCUUCAUGCUGACCAGGCAGUUCUAGAUGAGCGCUUGGAUAAGAGGGUGGAUGACAUGCUUGCUGCUGGGCUCUUGGAGGAACUAAGAGAUUUUCACAGACGCUAUAAUCAGAAGAAUGUUUCGGAAAAUAGCCAGGACUAUCAACAUGGUAUCUUCCAAUCAAUUGGCUUCAAGGAAUUUCACGAGUACCUGAUCACUGAGGGAAAAUGCACACUGGAGACUAGUAACCAGCUUCUAAAGAAAGGUAUUGAGGCUCUGAAACAAGUAACUAAGAGAUAUGCCCGGAAACAAAACCGAUGGGUUAAAAACCGUUUUUUGAGCAGACCUGGUCCCAUUGUCCCCCCUGUCUAUGGCUUAGAGGUAUCUGAUGUCUCGAAGUGGGAAGAGUCUGUUCUUGAACCUGCUCUUGAAAUCGUGCAAAGUUUCAUCCAGGGCCACAAGCCUACAGCCACUCCAAUAAAGAUGCCAUACAAUGAAGCUGAGAACAAGAGAAGUUAUCACCUGUGUGACCUCUGUGAUCGAAUCAUCAUUGGGGAUCGCGAAUGGGCAGCGCACAUAAAAUCCAAAUCCCACUUGAACCAACUGAAGAAAAGAAGAAGAUUGGACUCAGAUGCUGUCAACACCAUAGAAAGUCAGAGUGUUUCCCCAGACCAUAACAAAGAACCUAAAGAGAAGGGAUCCCCAGGGCAGAAUGAUCAAGAGCUGAAAUGCAGCGUUUAAGAGACAUGUCCAGUGGCCUUUGGAAAGGUGGUGGGGAUCCAGUUCAGGAGGGAGGGGUAUGUUUGUCUCCCAGUCUGGGCAAAGGAGUGCUAUGCGGAAUUCUCUGCAUAGCAGAAAAGCUCCCACCAUUUUCUUUUGAUGUGGUUUUAAAGUCUCACGUUCUCUAUAAUAGAAACAGCAGGUCUUGUCAGCUCCUUGUGUGGCUGAUGUGUCUGGAAAUGAUGUAGUUCAGGAAAGCAUUUUUUUUUUCUUUGAACCUUAAAGGUUCUAUUAUUAAAAGCAGCACAGAUUCCACAUUUUUAUACAUGAGGAUCUUCUUUGUGGUGAAUACCAGGAUUGACUGCAUCCCUUUAAAGAAGUUUUAUGUCCCUGACUCUGGCUAAAAUUAUCUAAUUUCCAGAUGCUUUUGUAGAUGACUGAAGUAUUUGUGAGCCACAUAUUGGGAGUUCUAGAUUUGAGUGAAUGGCAGGAAAGGGCCAUCUCCAUUGAGAUGAUUAAGUGAACCAAACUAGUUCUCAGAAUUCUACAGAGAAGGAGGGAAUCAGACUGAGGAAGCUGUGACAUAGGACUUGAAGACCAAAGACUUUGAAAUUUGCGAGCUGCUCAUGUGUGAGUUAUUAUCACUGCUGUCUUUCUAUUGAGUUACAAAUCUAUAUUUUUAUUGAAGUUUAAAUAAAGAAAAAAUUUACAAGAGCCUCUUUGAUCCUUAAAAAGAUAUACAAGUCCAUGCCUAGUUUAUACACAGUAUGCUCUGUUAUCAAUGUGAUAGCUUUUUCUCAAAUUUGACACUUUUUGUAGAUCAUGCUGUCUGUUCAUUUAUGUAGCGGGUGUUUAUUUAACACGUUAUAGUCCUUGAAGACAUCUAGAGAGGGUCUUUUAUUGGAGAUCUAUUACUUCCAAUUGAAGCCCUCUUUCUGGAGUGACCUGAGCUGCCAGCAAUGUUAAACAGAUACUUAUUUAUAUAUAACAUCAAAUAUAGCAUUUUUAGGGUAUAAUUCAGCAGCAUUAACUACAUUCACAAUGUUGUGCAAUCGUUGCCACUAUUUCCAAAACGUUUUUGUCACUCCAAACAAACUUUGUGCCCUUUAAGCGUUAACUCCCCAUUCAAAUACAUUUUGUUUGUGCAGAAUCUACUCUAUGAGAGGCCCUGAAUUAGGCUAAAGGGAAUGCAGAGAUGAGAUGUGGUUCUUGCCUUCAGGGAGCUUAUAAAUAAUUGCAUGUGUACACAAACACCAAUCCAGGCAAGACAGUAUCAAAGGCCGUAAGAGCUGUGUAGAAUUUCAGUUUAGAAGGAAGGGAAGGGAUCAUGGAAGGAGGAGCAUUUCUGCUGCACCUUGAAAAGCAAUUCUUGAUAAAUGUUUUGUUUCCUAUGCAUAUAAGACUUCAUAGAGGAGAAGGUAGAGUAAAAAAACUAUCUAACUUGAUUGACCUUUUUAAACAGUGCUGAAUUCCAGAGCCUCACCCACUUUUAACUGAUUUGAAUCUCAAAAAUAAAUUUAUUCUCUGGGCAAAGAAGUUUAUUAACUACUUUAGGACCUAACAAGGUGGGAAGCCACAUCUUCCCGGUGGGAGUGGAGAUGAGUACUUACUGUGAGCCAAGCAGUGCCAAGUCGUUUUUAUAUGUUAUCUUCUCACACAGCCCUGGGAGGGAGAUGCUGUUUCCUUUGCUGUUAACCAGGGAGGAAACUAAGGCUCAGCAAUGGAGUACAGCUAGCAAGCGGUAGAGCUGGAAUUGAGGUGAGGCUGGUAGACUCAAGCUAUUAAGCACUGUGUUAAGCUGGCAGUUUGUAGGGAAGAACCUUUAGUUUCUCUGAAAUAUUCUUCGUUCAAGUUGCUAAGUAUGUUUUAAAGCCUAAAAAGGUUUCAGUAGACAAGCAGGAAAAACUAGUUUUAAUAAUUGUACGUCAAAAAGCUUUUAAUCCUUCCAUCUGAAAUACCUGGAGCAGUAACUUCUCAUUGAACUCAUUGUUAUCUCUAUGGCAAUUGGAAAUCAGGCCUUUUUUACCAAAAAAAAAGUGUCUAAUAUUUAUGAAGCACUUACUAAGUGUAAGGCAGUGUGGUUGAGCCCACUGUUCAUAUUCUUAGAAAUUGUAAAUUCAGCCAAAUGAAAUUCCUUUAUCAGCAGCAAAGAGCCUGGGAAAGGCAGAACACUCACUAGAAAUCUGCCUGGUGCUCUGGUCUGAAGCAUUGCCCUGAGUAGAUUUCCCCUUUUGUGCCUGCUCCCCUAUGAAUGACUUCGCUGUUGAGUGUAGGGAAGGAAAGUAAUUUGUCUUGUGGUGGUCGUAAAUGUAGAGAUGAAAGAAUUCUUUAUCUCUUGUAUGGAUGGGGAAACUGAGGCCUAAAACAUGGAUGUUCCAGUCACAGAGCAAGGCAAAGCUGGGACAAACCUUAGAUCACCUUUCUUACUCUAUUACUAAAUCUCAUACCAAAUCUCAUUUGAGAGCUGAAAAGUACCAUAGAGCUUUGGGCUAUUUGCUCAGCCUGGAGUGAGAAUGAGGAAUGCCAUUUUGUACCAUCUGGCCAUAGCAAUCCCAAGGCAAGCAGAGCCCUCCAGUCCAGGUAUCCAGAGCCUCCAGUCCAUCACACCAGCAGUGCUAUCUAAAUGGCUUUGGCAAUUAAUUCCAAUACUCAGUGAGCUAUUAGGUUCAUCUGCUUCUGUCAGUAAAAAUCUUGAUUAGGCUUUAGAUACUUCUCACAGUUCAGGCAGUGCUGUUGUAAGUGGGUAGAAAGUACUUUGAUUCUGAAGAGAGAUCUAGACUUGAAAAUACUUUGCUUGAUUCUUAGGGCUAAGCAAGAGAACAGCUCAUCUGUAUUCCAGGAAUAUGGCUUGAUCCUUCCUAACUCUCAGUAAUUUUUUGUCCUCUCUUAGCUCUCUUUAGUUCCAAAGAGGAUUUUUUUGCUUAAAACAAAACAAAACACCCAGUAUAACAUUAAAAAAUAACAGUCCGGGAGUGGUGGCUCACGCCUGUAAUCCCAACGCUUUGGGUAACUGAGGCAGAAGGAUCACUCAAGCCUAGGAGUUUGAGACCAGCCUAGGCAACAUGGUGAGACCCAGUCAGCACAAAUAUAUACAUACAUACAUACUUACAUAUAUAUAUAUGUAUGCAUGCCGGGUAUGGUGGGUCAUGCCUAUAGUCCCAGCUACGUGGAAGGCUCAGGUAGGAGGAUGGCUUGGGCCUGGGAGAUUGAGGCUUCAGUGAAACAUGAUCAUGCCACUGCAUUCCAGCCUGGGUGGCAGAGCAAGACCAUGUUGCUCAAAAAGAAAAUAAAACUAACAACCCCCUCCCCCAAACACACAUGCAUGAAAUCAACCUUUUAUGAAUGCAGUGACUUGUCAAUAUCCCUAGCACCUAGACACAGUCAAAUAUUUGUUGAAUCAAUUGCAUGAAAGCAUAAAAACUAAGUAGGUCUCUACAUAAGUGAUCUGCUUCAAUUGUUAAAUACUUUUUAACCAGGAUGAAGAAAUUUUGGGAUAGCCACCAGCAGGAAUUUCUGUAUUUGAUUAUCACCUACUUGGGCAGUUAAGGCUGUUUUCUAAAAUGAUGGCUAACUGGUUAUUUGUAAAGCUACUCUGAAUGCUUACAAAGGAAGCUGCAUGUUUGUAUUAGUUCAGGUAAAAGGCUAAGUUGCUAUA